GUUUUCUGCCCGCGGUGCGCAGCGCUGAGUGUCGCGGCAGCAGCCUGUGCUUGCGCCUCAAGUCUUUCCGAGGGGCCAGUGGGCAGCGCGGGCCUCGGGGUCCUGGGGCGAGACGGUGAGCGUGGGGGCUGGGCCGGCGCCAGGGGCGCCGUUUCCUUCCCCCACGCAGCUCCGCGCGCCCGGGCCUCCACAUCGUCGCUAACGGAGCGUUGCGGCGCCGGCGACCCCUGGCGAGCCCGGGGCGGGACAGUGGCCAGGCCGGCCUGGGCCCAGCGCGUGGCCUCCGCCGUUUCGGGCUGUGCUGGGUGGAAGAUUAGGCUCCCCGGGCACGCCGUCCCCGCCGAGAGGCCUCAGCUUCGUGGCAGCGCCCUCGUCCUUCCAGCCCGCUCGAGGGUGGCCGCCAGGGCGCGAUGAAGGAAUGUGAGAAAGUGCUUAGCGCUCCAGCCGCUCCGAGGGAAGCCAGGUGGGAGGAGAUCCCGAAACGCUAAGGUUUUGACAGCGUUACAGUGAAUUCUCCGGCUGUAGAGAUUGGAGGAAGUCGGGAGAAAUUCGUCUCUAAGUUGUAAGCUUGUUCUAAAGACGAAGGGGAACUCCCUAGUGCUACAGGCUGUUUCAGGAAGCCAAUUAAUUUUGUACACAUAAUACUUAAUUACCUUCUAAUAAUUGGAGCAGAAGAUGAACCCAACUAAUCCUUUCAGUGGGCAGCAGCCUAGUGCUUUUUCGGCGUCUUCUAGUAAUGUAGGAACACUUCCAUCUAAGCCGCCAUUUCGAUUUGGUCAACCUUCUCUUUUUGGACAAAACAGUACCUUAUCUGGGAAGAGCUCGGGAUUUUCACAGGUAUCCAGCUUUCCAGCGUCUUCUGGAGUAAGUCAUUCCUCUUCAGUGCAAACAUUAGGGUUCACCCAAACCUCAAGUGUUGGACCCUUUUCUGGACUUGAGCACACUUCCACCUUUGUGGCUACCUCUGGGCCUUCAAGUUCAUCUGUGCUGGGAAACACAGGAUUUAGUUUUAAAUCACCCACCAGUGUUGGGGCUUUCCCAAGCACUUCUGCUUUUGGACAAGAAGCUGGAGAAAUAGUGAACUCUGGUUUUGGGAAAACAGAAUUCAGCUUUAAACCUCUGGAAAAUGCAGUGUUCAAACCAAUACUGGGGGCUGAAUCUGAGCCAGAGAAAACCCAGAGCCAAAUUGCUUCUGGGUUUUUUACAUUUUCCCACCCAAUUAGUAGUGCACCUGGAGGCCUGGCCCCUUUCUCUUUUCCUCAAGUAACAAGUAGUUCAGCUACCACUUCAAAUUUUACCUUUUCAAAACCUGUUAGUAGUAAUAAUUCAUUAUCUGCCUUUACCCCUGCUUUGUCAAACCAAAAUGUAGAGGAAGAGAAGAGAGGACCUAAGUCAAUAUUUGGAAGUUCUAAUAAUAGCUUCAGUAGCUUCCCUGUAUCAUCUGCGGUUUUGGGCGAACCUUUCCAGGCUAGCAAAGCAGGUGUCAGGCAGGGGUGUGAAGAAGCUGUUUCCCAGGUGGAACCACUUCCCAGCCUAAUGAAAGGACUGAAAAGGAAGGAGGACCAGGAUCGCUCCCCAAGGAGACAUGGCCACGAGCCAGCAGAAGAUUCGGAUCCUCUGUCCCGGGGCGAUCAUCCUCCAGACAAACGACCUGUCCGCCUGAAUCGACCCCGGGGAGGUACUUUAUUUGGUCGGACGAUACAGGAUGUUUUCAAAAGCAAUAAGGAAGUAGGUCGUCUGGGCAACAAGGAGGCCAAAAAGGAAACUGGCUUUGUUGAGUCUGCAGAAAGUGACCACAUGGCUAUCCCAGGAGGGAAUCAGUCUGUCCUGGCACCUUCCCGGAUUCCAGGUGUGAAUAAAGAGGAAGAAACUGAAAGUAGAGAGAAGAAAGAAGAUUCUCUAAGAGGAACUCCGGCGCGUCAGAGUAACAGAAGCGAGAGCACAGACAGUCUUGGGGGCUUGUCUCCCUCUGAAGUCACAGCCAUCCAGUGCAAGAACAUCCCUGACUACCUCAACGACAGGACCAUUCUGGAGAACCAUUUUGGCAAAAUUGCUAAAGUGCAGCGCAUCUUUACCAGGCGCAGCAAAAAGCUUGCAGUGGUACAUUUCUUUGAUCAUGCAUCUGCAGCCCUGGCUAGAAAGAAGGGGAAAAGUUUGCAUAAAGACAUGGCUAUCUUUUGGCACAGGAAGAAAAUAAGCCCCAAUAAGAAACCCUUUUCCCUGAAGGAGAAGAAACCAGGUGACGGUGAAGUCAGCCCGAGCACAGAGGAUGCACCCUUUCAGCACUCUCCUCUUGGCAAGGCCGCAGGGAGGACUGGUGCUAGCAGCCUCCUGAAUAAAAGCUCUCCAGUGAAGAAGCCAAGUCUUCUAAAGGCCCACCAAUUCGAGGGAGACUCUUUUGACUCAGCCUCCGAGGGCUCCGAGGGCCUCGGGCCAUGUGUGCUCUCCCUCAGUACCCUGAUAGGCACUGUGGCUGAGACAUCCAAGGAGAAGUACCGCCUGCUUGACCAGAGAGACAGGAUCAUGCGGCAAGCUCGGGUGAAGAGAACCGAUCUGGACAAAGCGAGGACUUUUGUUGGCACCUGCCUGGAUAUGUGUCCUGAGAAGGAGAGGUACAUGCGGGAGACCCGUAGCCAGCUGAGCGUGUUCGAAGUGGUCCCAGGGACUGACCAGGUGGACCACGCAGCAGCUGUGAAAGAGUACAGUCGGUCCUCGGCGGAUCAGGAGGAGCCCCUGCCCCACGAGCUGCGGCCCUUGCCAGUGCUCAGCAGGACCAUGGACUACCUGGUGACCCAGAUCAUGGACCAGAAGGAGGGCAGCCUGCGGGAUUGGUAUGACUUCGUGUGGAACCGCACGCGUGGCAUACGGAAGGAUAUCACGCAGCAGCACCUCUGUGACCCCCUGACGGUGUCCCUGAUUGAGAAGUGCACCCGGUUUCACAUCCACUGUGCCCACUUCAUGUGUGAGGAGCCCAUGUCCUCCUUUGAUGCCAAGAUCAAUAAUGAGAACAUGACCAAGUGCCUGCAGAGCCUGAAGGAGAUGUACCAGGACCUGAGAAACAAGGGUGUCUUCUGUGCCAGCGAAGCGGAGUUCCAGGGCUACAAUGUUCUGCUCAGUCUCAACAAGGGAGACAUCCUAAGAGAAGUACAACAGUUCCAUCCUGCUGUUAGAAACUCAUCUGAGGUGAAAUUUGCUGUUCAGGCUUUUGCUGCAUUGAACAGUAAUAAUUUUGUGAGAUUUUUCAAACUGGUCCAGUCAGCUUCUUACCUGAACGCUUGUCUUUUACACUGUUACUUCAGUCAGAUCCGCAAGGAUGCUCUCCGGGCGCUCAACUUUGCGUACACGGUGAGCACACAGCGAUCUACCAUCUUUCCCCUGGAUGGUGUGGUGCGCAUGCUGCUGUUCAGAGACUGUGAAGAGGCCACCGACUUCCUCACCUGCCACGGCCUCACCGUUUCCGACGGCUGUGUGGAGCUGAACCGGUCUGCAUUCCUGGAACCAGAGGGAUUAUCCAAGACCAGGAAGUCGGUGUUUAUUACUAGGAAGCUGACGGUGUCAGUCGGGGAAAUUGUGAACGGAGGGCCAUUGCCCCCCGUCCCUCGUCAUACCCCUGUGUGCAGCUUCAACUCCCAGAACAAGUACAUCGGGGAGAGCCUGGCCGCGGAGCUGCCCGUCAGCACCCAGAGACCCGGCUCCGACACAGUGGGCGGAGGGAGAGGAGAGGAGUGUGGUGUAGAGCCGGAUGCACCCCUGUCCAGUCUCCCACAGUCUCUACCAGCCCCUGCGCCCUCACCAGUGCCUCUGCCUCCUGUCCUGGCACUGACCCCGUCUGUGGCGCCCAGCCUCUUCCAGCUGUCUGUGCAGCCUGAACCACCGCCUCCAGAGCCCGUGCCCAUGUACUCUGACGAGGACCUGGCGCAGGUGGUGGACGAGCUCAUCCAGGAGGCCCUGCAGAGGGACUGUGAGGAAGUUGGCUCUGCGGGUGCUGCCUACGCAGCUGCCGCCCUGGGUGUUUCUAAUGCUGCUAUGGAGGAUUUGUUAACAGCUGCAACCACGGGCAUUUUGAGGCACAUUGCAGCUGAAGAAGUGUCUAAGGAAAGAGAGCGAAGGGAGCAGGAGAGGCAGCGGGCUGAAGAGGAAAGGUUGAAACAAGAGAGAGAGCUGGUGUUAAGUGAGCUGAGCCAGGGCCUGGCCGUGGAGCUGAUGGAACGCGUGAUGAUGGAGUUUGUGAGGGAAACCUGCUCCCAGGAGUUGAAGAAUGCAGUAGAGACAGACCAGAGGGUCCGUGUGGCCCGUUGCUGUGAGGAUGUCUGUGCCCACUUAGUGGACUUGUUUCUCGUGGAGGAAAUCUUCCAGACUGCAAAGGAGACCCUCCAGGAGCUUCAGUGCUUCUGCAAGUAUCUACAGCGGUGGAGGGAAGCUGUCACAGCCCGCAAGAAACUGAGGCGCCAAAUGCGGGCUUUCCCUGCUGCGCCCUGCUGCGUGGACGUGAGCGACCGGCUGAGGGCGCUGGCGCCCAGCGCAGAGUGCCCCAUUGCUGAAGAGAACCUGGCCAGGGGCCUCCUGGACCUGGGCCAUGCAGGGAGAUUGGGCAUCUCCUGCACCAGGUUAAGGCGGCUCAGAAACAAGACAGCUCACCAGAUGAAGGUUCAGCACUUCUACCAGCAGCUGCUGAGUGAUGUGGCAUGGGCGUCUCUGGACCUGCCAUCCCUCGUGGCUGAGCACCUCCCUGGGAGGCAGGAGCAUGUGUUUUGGAAGCUGGUGCUGGUGUUGCCGGAUGUAGAGGAGCAGUCCCCAGAGAGUUGUGGCAGAAUUCUAGCAAAUUGGUUAAAAGUCAAGUUCAUGGGAGAUGAAGGCUCAGUGGAUGACACAUCCAGCGAUGCUGGUGGGAUUCAGACGCUUUCGCUUUUCAACUCACUUAGCAGCAAAGGGGAUCAGAUGAUUUCUGUUAACGUGUGUAUAAAGGUGGCCCAUGGCGCCCUCAGUGAUGGUGCCAUUGAUGCUGUGGAGACACAGAAGGACCUCCUGGGAGCCAGUGGGCUCAUGCUGCUGCUUCCCCCCAAAAUGAAGAGUGAGGACAUGGCAGAGGAGGACGUGUACUGGCUGUCGGCCUUGCUGCAGCUCAAGCAGCUCCUGCAGGCUAAGCCCUUCCAGCCUGCGCUUCCUCUGGUGGUUCUUGUGCCUAGCCCAGGAGGGGACGCCGUUGAGAAGGAAGUAGAAGAUGGUCUGAUGCUACAGGACUUGGUUUCAGCUAAGCUGAUUUCAGAUUACACUGUUACCGAGAUCCCUGAUACCAUUAAUGAUCUACAAGGUUCAACUAAGGUUUUGCAAGCAGUGCAGUGGCUGGUUUCCCACUGCCCCCAUUCCCUUGACCUCUGCUGCCAGACUCUCAUUCAGUACGUCGAAGACGGGAUUGGCCAUGAGUUUAGUGGCCGCUUUUUCCAUGACAGAAGAGAGAGGCGUCUGGGCGGUCUUGCUUCUCAGGAGCCUGGCGCCAUCAUUGAGCUGUUUAACAGUGUGCUGCAGUUCCUGGCUUCUGUGGUGUCCUCUGAACAGCUGUGUGACCUGUCCUGGCCUGUCACUGAGUUUGCUGAGGCAGGGGGCAGCCGGCUGCUUCCUCACCUGCACUGGAAUGCCCCAGAGCACCUGGCCUGGCUGAAGCAGGCUGUGCUCGGGUUCCAGCUUCCGCAGAUGGACCUUCCACCCCUGGGGGCCCCCUGGCUCCCCGUGUGCUCCAUGGUUGUCCAGUACGCCUCCCAGAUCCCCAGCUCACGCCAGACACAGCCUGUCCUCCAGUCCCAGGUGGAGAACCUGCUCCACAGAACCUACUGUAGGUGGAAGAGCAAGAGUCCCUCCCCAGUCCAUGGGGCAGGCCCCUCGGUCAUGGAGAUCCCAUGGGAUGAUCUUAUCGCCUUGUGUAUCAACCACAAGCUGAGAGACUGGACGCCCCCCCGGCUUCCUGUUACAUCAGAGGCGCUGAGUGAAGAUGGUCAGAUAUGUGUGUAUUUUUUUAAAAACGAUUUGAAAAAAUAUGAUGUUCCUUUGUCGUGGGAACAAGCCAGGUUGCAGACGCAGAAGGAGCUACAGCUGAGAGAGGGACGUUUGGCAAUAAAGCCUUUUCAUCCUUCUGCAAACAAUUUUCCCAUACCAUUGCUUCACAUGCACCGUAACUGGAAGAGGAGCACAGAGUGUGCUCAAGAGGGGAGGAUUCCCAGCACAGAGGAUCUGAUGCGAGGAGCUUCUGCUGAGGAGCUCUUGGCGCAGUGUUUGUCGAGCAGUCUGCUGCUGGAGAAAGAAGAGAACAAGAGGUUUGAAGAUCAGCUUCAGCAAUGGUUGUCUGAAGACUCAGGAGCAUUUACGGAUUUAACUUCCCUUCCCCUCUAUCUUCCUCAGACUCUAGUGUCUCUUUCUCACACUAUUGAACCUGUGAUGAAAACAUCUGUAACUACUAGCCCACAGAGUGACAUGAUGAGGGAGCAACUGCAGCUGUCAGAGGCGACAGGAACGUGUCUAGGCGAACGACUAAAGCACCUGGAAAGGCUGAUCCGGAGUUCAAGGGAAGAGGAAGUUGCCUCUGAGCUCCAUCUCUCUGCGCUGCUAGACAUGGUGGACAUUUGAGCAGCCUGACCUGUGGGGAGGGGGUCUCUCCCGAAGAGUUUCUGUUUUUACUCAAAAUAAUGUUAUUCUCAGAUGCUUGAUGCACUGUUGGAAAUGUGAUUAAUUUAAUCAUGCAGAUAAACCAUUUAAAUGUCA